AGUAGCCAGACAUGAGCUGUGAGGGUCAAGCACAGCUAUCCAUCAGAUGAUCUACUUUCAGCCUUCCUGAGUCCCAGACAAUAGAAGACAGGUGGCUGUACCCUUGGCCAAGGGUAGGUGUGGCAGUGGUGUCUGCUGUCACUGUGCCCUCAUUGGCCCCCAGCAAUCAGACUCAACAGACGGAGCAACUGCCAUCCGAGGCUCCUGAACCAGGGCCAUUCACCAGGAGCAUGCGGCUCCCUGAUGUCCAGCUCUGGCUGGUGCUGCUGUGGGCACUGGUGCGAGCACAGGGGACAGGGUCUGUGUGUCCCUCCUGUGGGGGCUCCAAACUGGCACCCCAAGCAGAACGAGCUCUGGUGCUGGAGCUAGCCAAGCAGCAAAUCCUGGAUGGGUUGCACCUGACCAGUCGUCCCAGAAUAACUCAUCCUCCACCCCAGGCAGCGCUGACCAGAGCCCUCCGGAGACUACAGCCAGGGAGUGUGGCUCCAGGGAAUGGGGAGGAGGUCAUCAGCUUUGCUACUGUCACAGACUCCACUUCAGCCUACAGCUCCCUGCUCACUUUUCACCUGUCCACUCCUCGGUCCCACCACCUGUACCAUGCCCGCCUGUGGCUGCACGUGCUCCCCACCCUUCCUGGCACUCUUUGCUUGAGGAUCUUCCGAUGGGGACCAAGGAGGAGGCGCCAAGGGUCCCGCACUCUCCUGGCUGAGCACCACAUCACCAACCUGGGCUGGCAUACCUUAACUCUGCCCUCUAGUGGCUUGAGGGGUGAGAAGUCUGGUGUCCUGAAACUGCAACUAGACUGCAGACCCCUAGAAGGCAACAGCACAGUUACUGGACAACCGAGGCGGCUCUUGGACACAGCAGGACACCAGCAGCCCUUCCUAGAGCUUAAGAUCCGAGCCAAUGAGCCUGGAGCAGGCCGGGCCAGGAGGAGGACCCCCACCUGUGAGCCUGCGACCCCCUUAUGUUGCAGGCGAGACCAUUACGUAGACUUCCAGGAACUGGGAUGGCGGGACUGGAUACUGCAGCCCGAGGGGUACCAGCUGAAUUACUGCAGUGGGCAGUGCCCUCCCCACCUGGCUGGCAGCCCAGGCAUUGCUGCCUCUUUCCAUUCUGCCGUCUUCAGCCUCCUCAAAGCCAACAAUCCUUGGCCUGCCAGUACCUCCUGUUGUGUCCCUACUGCCCGAAGGCCCCUCUCUCUCCUCUACCUGGAUCAUAAUGGCAAUGUGGUCAAGACGGAUGUGCCAGAUAUGGUGGUGGAGGCCUGUGGCUGCAGCUAGCAAGAGGACCUGGGGCUUUGGAGUGAAGAGACCAAGAUGAAGUUUCCCAGGCACAGGGCAUCUGUGACUGGAGGCAUCAGAUUCCUGAUCCACACCCCAACCCAACAACCACCUGGCAAUAUGACUCACUUGACCCCUAUGGGACCCAAAUGGGCACUUUCUUGUCUGAGACUCUGGCUUAUUCCAGGUUGGCUGAUGUGUUGGGAGAUGGGUAAAGCGUUUCUUCUAAAGGGGUCUACCCAGAAAGCAUGAUUUCCUGCCCUAAGUCCUGUGAGAAGAUGUCAGGGACUAGGGAGGGAGGGAGGGAAGGCAGAGAAAAAUUACUUAGCCUCUCCCAAGAUGAGAAAGUCCUCAAGUGAGGGGAGGAGGAAGCAGAUAGAUGGUCCAGCAGGCUUGAAGCAGGGUAAGCAGGCUGGCCCAGGGUAAGGGCUGUUGAGGUACCUUAAGGGAAGGUCAAGAGGGAGAUGGGCAAGGCGCUGAGGGAGGAUGCUUAGGGGACCCCCAGAAACAGGAGUCAGGAAAAUGAGGCACUAAGCCUAAGAAGUUCCCUGGUUUUUCCCAGGGGACAGGACCCACUGGGAGACAAGCAUUUAUACUUUCUUUCUUCUUUUUUAUUUUUUUGAGAUCGAGUCUCGCUCUGUCACCAGGCUGGAGUGCAGUGACACGAUCUUGGCUCACUGCAACCUCCGUCUCCUGGGUUCAAGUGAUUCUUCUGCCUCAGCCUCCCGAGCAGCUGGGAUUACAGGCGCCCACUAAUUUUUGUAUUCUUAGUAGAAACGAGGUUUCAACAUGUUGGCCAGGAUGGUCUCAAUCUCUUGACCUCUUGAUCCACCCGACUUGGCCUCCCGAAGUGAUGAGAUUAUAGGCGUGAGCCACCGCGCCUGGCUUAUACUUUCUUAAUAAAAAGGAGAAAGAAAAUCAACAAAUGUGAGUCAUAAAGAAGGGUUAGGGUGAUGGUCCAGAGCAACAGUUCUUCAAGUGUACUCUGUAGGCUUCUGGGAGGUCCCUUUUCAGGGGUGUCCACAAAGUCAAAGCUAUUUUCAUAAUAAUACUAACAUGUUAUUUGCCUUUUGAAUUCUCAUUAUCUUAAAAUUGUAUUGUGGAGUUUUCCAGAGGCCGUGUGACAUGUGAUUACAUCAUCUUUCUGACAUCAUUGUUAAUGGAAUGUGUGCUUGUA